GAAGGCGAAGUGGGAGCUUGCACAUCACUACGUGAAAGCAGGGGCAAGAGAGAGAGCAGGGAGUGCCACGCACUUUUAAACAACCAGAUCUUGCAAGAACUCACUUGCUAUCACGAGGACAGUAACAGGGGAUGCCACAAAACCAUGGGUGAAGUUGAGAGCAAUGGCCCAACCUCAGCUGUAUCUACCAGAACCCUUUAAGAUUGCCUACAGAAAAGUUGGACAGUGCCGAAGAUUCCAGCAACUCAAGAAGAAAAAUGGCUCAUUCAAAAGGAAGGGGAUAGAAAGAUGGCAUAGAGCUGUGUCUACCAACUUACUAAAACAAAAUGUAUUGGUCCCUAAAGAGGAAUCAUCCAGUGAUAGUGACAUGGGAUUUCAUGAAAGCCAGCAAAAUCAGAAAAGUAAUUUGAAGACGAAAGUGAAGACUGCUUUUGGGAGGAUGCUGUCCUACAAGUAUAGAAGCAAGCCAGCAUGUGCCAGCCAAGAGGGCUCCACUGACCAUAAAGAAGCCCUCCUGUCAAACACGCAGAGCCUUCUCCCUAGGAUUGUCAAGGAGUUUUCAUCUCCCAAGUUAUUUACAGCAAAAAUGAGAAAGCUCUCAGAGAAUGCGACUAUACAACUUGAUGUUGUAGAGGCAGAGACAGAGGAGAUAACCCAGGGAAACACACUCCUUCGGGCCAGGAGAACCACCAAGCGGUUAUCUGUGACAUCUCUUCCUUCAGGACUGCAAAAGGGGCCAUAUUCACCAAAAAAGAGACCACACUUUCCAGCACUUAAAAAAAAGAAGCGUGGCAUGGAAAACAUCCUUCGAAAAUCAGAUUUGACAGUAGGAAAGCUUCAAAUGCAGGUGGAUGACCUCAUAGAAACAGUGACUGAUAAAUCCAUGAAGCUACUGGCCCAAAGACAUGCUGAGCUUCAACAGUGUGAGUUUCUGGGGGAUGAAAUUCUUCAGUCUUCUAAACAGUUCCAGAGGAUAUCCAAGAGAACCAUGAGGAAGUAUAAAUUAAAAAAUGUGUGUUUCCCAUGUACCUGCUGCUGCUUCUGACUUUGUUCCUGAUUCUUUAAAAGUUAUCUUCCCUAGGCUGGCCGUGGUGGCUCACGCCUGUAAUCUCAGCACUUUGGGAGGCCGAGCGAGUGGAUCACUUGAUGUCUGGAGUUCAAAACCAGCCUGGCCAACAUGGUGAAACCCUGUCUCUACUAAAAAUACAAAAAUUAUCCAGGAGUGGUGGCGGGCGCCUCUAAUCCCAGCUACUCGGGAGGCUGAGGCAGGAGAAUUGCUUGAACCUGGGAGGCAGAGGCUGCAGUGAGCCGAGAUCGCACCACUGCACUCCAGCCUGGGCGACAGCACAAGACUCCAUCUCGAAAAUAAAAAAAUAAAUAAAAGUUGUCUUCCAAGAGAUUCUUAUCUUUUGGUACUUAAUCCUGA